GUUCCGGCCAAGCCGCUUCAGCGGGGGACGUAGCCAUGAAGGAAGAGAAGGAGCACAGGCCUAAGGAGAAGCGAGUAACCCUGUUAACCCCCGCCGGGGCCACAGGCAGCGGUGGUGGGACCUCGGGGGACAGCUCCAAGGGGGAAGAUAAGCAGGAUCGCAACAAGGAGAAGAAAGAAGCGCUGAGCAAGGUGGUAAUUCGAAGAUUACCUCCCACUUUGACCAAGGAGCAGCUUCAGGAACAUCUUCAACCUAUGCCUGAGCAUGAUUAUUUUGAGUUUUUUUCUAAUGAUACGAGUUUGUAUCCUCAUAUGUAUGCCAGAGCAUACAUCAACUUUAAAAACCAAGAGGACAUUAUUUUGUUCAGGGAUCGCUUUGAUGGUUAUGUAUUCCUUGACAAUAAAGGUCAGGAAUAUCCCGCUAUAGUAGAAUUUGCACCUUUUCAAAAAGCUGCAAAAAAGAAGACUAAGAAAAGAGAUACCAAAGUCGGGACUAUCGAUGAUGAUCCAGAAUAUAGAAAGUUUUUGGAAAGUUAUGCCACAGAUAAUGAGAAAAUGACAUCUACUCCAGAGACACUGCUAGAGGAAAUAGAAGCAAAAAAUAGAGAAUUAAUAGCUAAAAAGACAACCCCACUUUUGAGCUUCCUGAAAAACAAGCAGAGAAUGAGAGAAGAAAAGAGAGAAGAAAGGAGGAGGAGAGAAAUAGAAAGAAAAAGACAAAGAGAAGAAGAGAGGAGGAAAUGGAAAGAAGAAGAGAAACGAAAAAGGAAAGAUAUAGAAAAGCUAAAGAAGAUAGACAGAAUUCCAGAAAGGGACAAAUUAAAGGAUGAACCAAAGAUUAAGGUACACAGGUUUCUGUUACAAGCUGUGAAUCAGAAAAAUCUGCUCAAGAAGCCAGAAAAAGGAGAUGAAAAAGAAUUGGACAAAAGAGAAAAAGCCAAGAAAUUGGACAAAGAGAAUCUCAGUGAUGAAAGAGCCAGUGGGCAAAGUUGUACAUUGCCCAAGCGUUCUGAUAGCGAACUUAAAGAUGAAAAACCAAAGAGACCUGAAGAUGAGAGCGGCAGAGACUAUAGGGAGAGGGAACGGGAAUAUGAACGAGAUCAGGAGCGCAUACUUCGAGAAAGAGAGAGGCUGAAGCGGCAAGAAGAAGAGCGCCGUAGGCAGAAGGAGCGCUAUGAGAAAGAGAAGACUUUUAAGAGAAAAGAAGAAGAAAUGAAAAAAGAGAAAGACACACUUCGGGAUAAAGGAAAGAAGGCUGAAAGUACAGAAUCAAUAGGCAGCUCAGAAAAAACUGAAAAGAAAGAAGAAGUGGUCAAGAGAGAUCGAAUAAGAAACAAGGAUCGUCCAGCGAUGCAGCUUUACCAACCAGGAGCUCGAAGCCGAAAUCGACUCUGUCCCCCUGAUGACAGCACCAAGUCUGGAGAUUCAGCAGCAGAAAGGAAGCAGGGUCGUCCAGGGAUGCAGUCUUACCAUCCAGGAGUUCAAAGCCACUAUCAACACUAUUUUCCUGAUGACAGCACCAACUAUAGAUACUCACCAGUAGAAGAAAAGCAGGAAAGUAGUAUUAGCUGUAGAAAAGAAGGAGGAGGCCAGGCGUGGUGGCGCACACCUGUAAUCCCAGCACUUUGGGAGGCUGAGGCGGGCAGAUCGCAUGAGGACUGUCCAUGGAUGCAGUGUUACCAUCGAGGAGCUCGAGGCCGAGGUCGACUCUGGCACCCUGAUGACAAGUCUGGAGAUUCAGCAGUAGAAAGAAAGCAGAAUCAUCCAGGGAUGCAGCGUUACCAUCCAGGAGCUCGAAGCCAAGGUCGACUCUCGCACCCUGAUGACAUAACCAAGUCUGGAGAUUCAGCAGUAGAAAGAAAGCAGGAUCAUCCAGGGAUGAAGCUUUACCAUCCAGGAGCUCGAAGCCCAGGUCGAUUCUGGUGGCAAGAUGGCAGCACCAAUCUGGAGAUUCAGCAGUAGAAAGAAAGCAGGAAAGUGAUAUUAACCAUAGAAAAGAAGGAGGAAGGGAGUGUUAAGUCCAGAUGGCCUUAGGUGUACUGACUGUCUAGGCAGCCAAAGAGCACACGUUAAGCAAUCCAGAAGUGCCUUCAGGGCAAAGAAUAGAGAGAAAGGGGGUGGUUGUGCUGGUGGGGUACACUGCAGAGGAGUAAGUCUUGUGUCAAAGCAGGAAUCUGAUCAGAGGUUCAGAAUUGGAAGUACAAUUUCAUUGCUUUUGCAAUUUAUACAAAUUAAUUUUAGUGUCAGAAAAAGCUGAUGGUGAGGACAUGCAUUGCAAUUUGCAGGGAAAUGUCAAGUGAGGACUUCAUUACGUAUGACACGAGAGAAAAGUAAGAGCUGGUUCUAAAAUCAAAAGCUGUUGUUCAUCCCGAGUUGAAUUUUCUUUUUUUUUUUUCUUUUUUUUUUUUUUUUUUUUUUUUAGACAGGGUCUCACCCUGUUGCCCAGCCUGGAGUACAGUGGCUCAAUGUCGGUUCACUGCAACCUCCACCUCCUGGGUUCAACUGAUUCUCCUGCCUCAGCCUCCCGAGUAGCUGGGAUUACAGGUGCCCGCCACCUUGCCUGGCUAAUUUUUGUAUUUUUAGUAGACAUGGGGUUUCACCACGUUGGCCACGCUGGUCUUGAACUCCUGACCUCAGGUGAUUCCCCCCGCUUCGGCCUUCCAAAGUGCUGGGAUUACAGGUAUGAGCCACCGUGCCCGUCCAUUCCAAUCUAGUUUUAUUGCAUUGUUGAUGAUAACUGUUGACUUUGGGAAGUGUAGAAGCAACAAGCAUGUCCUUGUAGUAUAAGUACAGUGAAGGAUAGAACAAACUUUUGUUGGUGCCAAAAUUUAAAUAGUCAUGUUACUUCUGCAUCUAAUGUCCUAAAGUUUAAGGAUUACUUUUAGUUUUUUGUUUGCUUACAUGAGCUUAGCAUGAAGAAUAUUUUCAAACAUCUGCUUUUAUCUUCAGCUUUUUUUAUUUUUUAUUAUACUUUAAGUUUUAGGGUACAUGUGCACAUUGUGCAGGUUAGUUACAUAUGUAUACAUGUGCCAUGCUGGUGUGCUGCACCCACUAACUCGUCAUCUAGCAUUAGGUAUAUCUCCCAAUGCUAUCCCUCCCCCCUCCCCCAACCCCACCACAGUCCCCAGAGUGUGAUAUUCCCCUUCCUGUGUCCAUGUGAUCUCAUUGUUCAAUUCCCACCUAUGAGUGAGAAUAUGCGGUGUUUGGUUUUUUGUUCUUGCAAUAGUUUACUGAGAAUGAUGAUUUCCAGUUUCAUCCAUGUCCCUACAAAGGACAUGAACUCAUCAUUUUUUAUGGCUGCAUAGUAUUCCAUGGUGUAUAUGUGCCACAUUUUCUUAAUCCAGUCUAUCAUUGUUGGACAUUUGGGUUGGUUCCAAGUCUUUGCUAUUGUGAAUAAUGCCGCAGUAAACAUACGUGUGCAUGUGUCUUUAUAGCAGCAUGAUUUAUAGUCCUUUGGGUAUAUACCCAGUAAUGGGAUGGCUGGGUCAAAUGGUAUUUCUAGUUCUAGAUCCCUGAGGAAUCGCCACACUGACUUCCACAAUGGUUGAACUAGUUUACAGUCCCACCAACAGUGUAAAAGUGUUCCUAUUUCUCCACAUCCUCUCCAGCACCUGUUGUUUCCUGACUUUUUAAUGAUUGCCAUUCUAACUGGUGUGAGAUGGUAUCUCAUUGUGGUUUUGAUUUGCAUUUCUCUGAUGGCCAGGGAUGAUGAGCAUUUUUUCAUGUGUUUUUUGGCUGCAUAAAUGUCUUCUUUUGAGAAGUGUCUGUUCAUGUCCUUAGCCCACUUUUUGAUGGGGUUGUUUUUUCUUGUAAAUUUAUUUGAGGUCAUUGUAGAUUCUGGAUAUUAGCCCUUCGUCAGAUGAGUAGGUUGCGAAAAUUUUCUCCCAUUUUGUAGGUUGCCUGUUCACCCUGAUGGUAGUUUCUUUUGCUGUGCAGAAGCUCUUUAGUUUAAUUAGAUCCCAUUGGUAGUCCUUGUUUGAUUCUUGACAAUCCAGUGUGUGUUUUAUCUUAGGUCUCAUGAUCUGAGUGUGUACCCUCUCCAGGAAGGAAACUGCAUCAAUGUCUGUUCCUGUUAAAUAGCAACUUUUAGUCUCAGCUUGUUUUGUUUUGAUGUCAAUAAAUAGUAACAACAUUCAA